GGGCGAGGGGUGGUUGCGGCGGAGGACGCAACCGAGCGGUGAGGCGCGUGGGCCUUCGGGGGUCGAGGUCGUGGUAGUGGGGCGCGGGGAGGCCAAGACCCGGCCGAGGGGGGCGGGCGGGCCAGGGAGCAGCCCAGCCCGGGGCGUGCGCGACCUGGGCUCGCUUCCCAGCCCGACUGUGGCCGCCUGCUCUGGCGCCCCUUCUGGACUCUCGGGCCUGGCGCUCGCGGCCAAAACUGACUUCAAAGUGUGGGGAGGGUUCCUCUUCCCGGGACGCAGCCUUCCCGGGCAUUGGCAGACGGUGCCCCGGUUAGACAGAGCCGCUGACCACCCCGCCCACCCCCGAGGCUGGACGCACGGAUGCACACCUGGUCCUGGGAGAGACAGGCGCCCCUUCCUUUCCGCACCCCGCCGCCCCCCUCUCCCCCCCGCCGGCUUCAGAUGCAGCCACCACUAAUCCUGGGAGGGACAGACACACGGACAGGGCCUGCGGCCUCACCAUGGACCCAGAAUGCGCCCAGCUGCUCCCGGCUCUCUGUGCUGUUCUGGUAGAUCCCAGGCAGCCGGUGGCAGAUGACACCUGUUUGGAGAAGCUCCUGGACUGGUUUAAAACGGUCACUGAAGGAGAGUCCAGUGUCGUGCUGCUGCAGGAGCACCCCUGCCUGGUGGAGCUGCUGUCCCAUGUGCUGAAAGUCCAGGACCUGAGUUCUGGGGUCCUCUCCUUCUCACUGCGCCUGGCAGGAACCUUCGCAGCCCAGGAAAACUGCUUCCAGUAUCUUCAGCAGGGGGAGUUACUACCAGGGCUCUUUGGGGAGCCAGGACCCCUCGGCCGAGCAACCUGGGCCGUCCCCACCGUGCGCAGCGGCUGGAUCCAGGGCCUGCGCUCCCUGGCACAGCACCCCAGCGCCCUGCGCUUCCUGGCCGACCAUGGUGCGGUCGACACCAUCUUCUCCCUGCAGGGAGACUCCAGCCUGUUUGUGGCCUCGGCGGCCAGUCAGCUCCUGGUGCACGUCCUGGCUUUGUCCAUGCGAGGUGGAGCCGAGGGGCAGCCCUGCCUGCCGGGGGGUGACUGGCCCGCGUGUGCCCAGAAGAUCAUGGAUCACGUUGAAGAGUCCUUGUGCUCCGCGGCCACCCCCAAGGUCACUCAGGCCCUGAACGUCCUGACCACGACCUUCGGGCGCUGCCAGAGCCCCUGGACGGAAGCCCUGUGGGUGCGGCUGAGUCCCCGCGUGGCCUGUCUGCUGGAGAGAGACCCCAUCCCCGCCGCACACUCGUUCGUGGACCUGCUUCUCUGUGUGGCUCGUUCUCCCGUGUUCAGUUCUUCCGACGGCAGCCUGUGGGAGACAGUGGCGCGGGCUCUGAGCUGCCUGGGUCCCACCCACAUGGGACCCCUGGCUUUGGGGAUCCUGAAGCUCGAGCACUGUCCACAGGCACUGAGGACCCAGGCCUUCCAGGUCCUUCUCCAGCCCCUGGCCUGUGUCCUGAAGGCCACGGUUCAGGCCCCCGGACCCCCAGGCUUGCUGGACGGGACGGCAGACGAUGCCACGACGGUGGACACACUCCUGGCCUCCAAGUCGUCCUGCGCCGGCCUCCUGUGCCGCACCCUGGCUCACCUGGAGGAGCUGCAGCCGCUGCCCCAGCGCCCUUCACCGUGGCCCCAGGCGUCUCUACUGGGGGCUACAGUGACUGUCCUGCGGCUCUGUGACGGCUCGGCUGCCCCUGCCUCCAGUGUGGGGGGCCACCUCUGUGGGACCCUGGCGGGCUGCGUCCGGGUCCAGCGAGCAGCCCUCGACUUCCUGGGGACGCUGUCACAGGGGACAGGCCCCCAGGAGCUGGUGACGCAGGCGCUUGCUGUCCUCCUGGAGUGCCUCGAGAGCCCCGGCUCCAGCCCCACGGCCUCUGCGGAUGGGGCCUUCACACAGGGCCACAGAGCUGCUGCUCAGAGAGCUUCACGAUGCAGCCCACCCUAUCUGCUCCAGGUUCUGAAGAAGGCCUUCCAGGCCACGCUCAGGUGGCUCCUGAGCUCACCCAAGACCCCCGGCUGCUCUGAUCUCGGCCCCCUCAUCCCGCAGUUCCUCAGAGAGCUGUUCCCUGUGCUGCAGAAACGCCUGUGCCACCCCUGCUGGGAGGUGAGGGACUCCGCCCUCGAGUUCCUGACCCAGCUGAGCAGGCACUGGGGAGGACAGGCUGACUUCAGAUGCGCACUCUUGGCUUCAGAGGUGCCUCAGCUGGCCCUGCAGCUCCUCCAGGACCCUGAGAGUUAUGUCCGAGCGAGUGCAGUGACCGCCAUGGGGCAGCUGUCCAGCCAGGGCCUGCACGCCCCCACCAGCCCUGAGCAUGCAGAGGCCCGGCAGAUGGGUAAACUGAGGAUUGGAGGGCCGUGUGCUCACUGCGCAGCAUGGGAAGGUGUCAGAGCGGGCUGUGGCCCUAGACUGCAUGUCCGGGGCCAGCCCCCAUCAUGUACCGGAGUCCUGUUGCGGGAGCCUCGCUCCUGCCACCCCACCAACCAUCCGCACUUGCUCCCUGUCCCCCAGAGCCUGUUCCUGGAGCUCCUGCACAUCCUCUCCGUAGACUCGGAGGGCUUCCCACGGCGGGCGGUCAUGCAAGUCUUCACUGAGUGGCUGCGGGACGGCCACGCCGACGCGGCCCAGGACACGGAGCAGUUCGUGGCCACUGUGCUGCAGGCGGCGAGCCGAGACCUGGACUGGGAGGUCCGCGCCCAGGGCCUGGAGCUGGCCCUCGUGUUCCUGGGCCAGACUUUGGGGCCGCCGCGUACCCACUGCCCCUAUGCCGUGGCCCUACCCGAGGUGGCCCCAGCCCAGCCACUCACCGAGGCACUGAGGGCUCUCUGCCACGUGGGGCUCUUUGACUUCGCCUUUUGUGCCUUGUUUGACUGCGACCGCCCUGUGGCGCAGAAGUCUUGUGACCUCCUUCUCUUCCUGAGGGACAAGAUUGCUUCCUACAGCAGCCUGCGGGAGGCCAGGGGCAGCCCCAACACUGCCUCCGCAGAGGCCACCCUGCCGAGGUGGCGGGCGGGUGAGCAGGCCCAGCCCCCAGGGGACCAGGAGCCUGAGGCUGUGCUGGCCAUGCUCAGGUCCCUAGACCUGGAGGGCCUGCGGAGCACGCUGGCCGAGAGCAGCGACCACGUGGAAAAGAGUCCCCAGUCCCUCCUGCAGGACAUGCUGGCCACGGGAGGCUUCCUGCAGGGGGACGAGGCCGACUGCUACUGAGCAGAACCAGAGUCUGCCACUGGGGCUCAGGACCAAGGGAGGCAGCACCAUGUCCUUCUGUGGGACACUGCCAGCCCCAGGGCUCCAGCCCAGCCCGGUGGAUCCUCUGGGGAAGCCAGGACCAGGAGAGAAGCAAGGUCAAGAAAUCCCACAGUUUGAUGUAUUAAAGAAAUGACUUAUUUCUACUCAAAAUAAAUGGCAUUGAAGUCUUUCUUUAACCCUUUUUGAGUUAAUUUAAUAAUAAUGAUCUGAGACAAGG